GAAAUGUUUGCAAGGCAGUGUGGUUUUCAGGAAUAUAUUGAAAUCUUUUAUGGUUUUAUUAGAAAAUUUGAACAAGUGAUCCUUGGAGUAAGUAGGAGUUUAUUGUCAAAGAAAGAGAAGUUAAACCACAUGAAGUUUGAGCUUUAUCUAUUAGAUUUUAUUUAAAAGCAAUGCAGAUUGUGUUAUCUAGUACUUCAGUGCUAAUGGUAGUAUUCUAAGAAAUCAGAUUUUUUCAUUGUGAGUCUUUGAUUUAAUAACCACUUAGCUUAGUUUUUUUUUGGUUUUUUUUUUUUUUUUUUAAUUGGUGGGUCUCAGGGCAUCCCAGCAUCUGACAGGUCCUUUUGAUCCCAAUAAGCAUUUUUGAUCCCAAUACACUUUUAUACUUGAGAAGAUCAUCACUUAGCCCUAUAUUAAGGAAUCUAGAGAAGACGGGGAGGCAGGUACCAUUGAUUACUGAGCACUAGAGAGUUAACUCUUCCUCUCUUAUGAAAUUAGAAAGCAUUCAAAAGUUAUCUUUAGAACUUUCCAGCUGUUAGUAUAGCAUGUGUAAAAUUUGUAUGUUUAAGCCAGUGUCUCCCUGGCAAAUGCAAAUUUCUUUUCUUUUUUAAUUUAUUUUUUUUGUUUGUUUUAGAGGUAGGGUCUCAUUAUGUUGCCCAGGCUGGUCUCAAACUCCGAGCUCAAGCAAUCCAACCACCUUGGCCACCCAAAUUGCUGGGAUUAUAGACGUGAGCCACCACACUUGGCCUUCCCCUGGCAAAUUUCUGUAAUGUUUGAAAUCAGCCUAUGGACCAGCUCUCAUUGAACACUGUCUUUUAGAAAAUGGAUUCUCGGGUAAUGUCAAAGUGGAUGAAAAACUUGAAACUAAAGGGAUAUAUCAUUCAGAAAAGAGAAAUAAAACCAAGCUUGGAAGCAGAUAAACCAGUUGAAGACAUACUGACGUAUGAGGAAUUUCAUCCUUUCUUGUUUUCUCAACAUUCACAAUGUCCAUAUAUAGAAUUUGAAUCAUUUGACAAGGCGGUGGAUGAAUUUUAUUCCAAGAUAGAAGGCCAGAAAAUUGACUUAAAAGCUUUACAACAGGAAAAGCAAGCAUUGAAGAAAUUAGAUAAUGUUCGAAAGGAUCACGAAAACAGAUUGGAAGCUCUUCAGCAGGCUCAGGAAAUAGACAAACUGAAAGGAGAGCUCAUAGAAAUGAACCUACAAAUAGUUGACAGAGCCAUUCAGGUAGUUCGAAGUGCUUUAGCUAACCAGAUAGAUUGGACAGAAAUUGGGUUAAUUGUGAAAGAAGCCCAGGCUCAAGGAGACCCUGUUGCAAGUGCAAUCAAAGAAUUAAAACUACAAACAAACCAUGUUACAAUGCUGCUAAGAAAUCCAUACUUGUUAUCAGAGGAGGAAGAUGAUGAUGUUGAUGGUGACGUCAAUGUUGAGAAAAAUGAAACUGAACCACCAAAAGGAAAAAAGAAAAAACAAAAGAAUAAACAGCUGCAGAAGCCUCAGAAAAAUAAGCCCUUACUUGUAGAUGUUGAUCUCAGCUUGUCAGCAUAUGCCAAUGCCAAAAAGUAUUAUGAUCACAAGAGAUAUGCUGCUAAGAAAACACAAAAGACUGUUGAAGCUGCUGAGAAGGCAUUCAAGUCAGCAGAAAAGAAAACAAAGCAAACAUUAAAAGAAGUUCAGACUGUUACCUCUAUUCAAAAAGCAAGAAAAGUAUAUUGGUUUGAGAAAUUUCUGUGGUUCAUUAGCUCAGAGAACUAUCUAAUUAUAGGUGGACGAGAUCAGCAACAGAAUGAAAUAAUUGUGAAAAGAUACUUGACACCAGGAGACAUUUAUGUACAUGCUGAUCUUCAUGGAGCUACUAGCUGUGUAAUUAAGAAUCCAACAGGAGAACCCAUCCCCCCACGGACCUUGACUGAAGCUGGCACAAUGGCACUUUGCUACAGUGCUGCUUGGGAUGCACGAGUUAUCACUAGUGCUUGGUGGGUGUACCAUCAUCAGGUAUCUAAAACAGCACCAACUGGAGAAUAUUUGACAACAGGAAGCUUCAUGAUAAGAGGAAAAAAGAAUUUUCUUCCUCCCUCAUAUCUAAUGAUGGGGUUUAGCUUCCUUUUUAAGGUAGAUGAGUCUUGUGUUUGGAGACAUCAGGGUGAACGAAAAGUCAGAGUACAGGAUGAAGACAUGGAGACACUGGCAAGUUGUACAAGUGAACUCAUAUCAGAAGAAAUGGAACAAUUAGAUGGAGGUGACACGAGCAGUGAUGAGGAUAAAGAAGAACAUGAAACUCCUGUGGAAGUAGAACUCAUGACUCAGGUUGACCAAGAGGAUAUCACUCUUCAGAGUGGCAGAGAUGAACUAAAUGAGGAGCUCAUUCAGGAAGAAAGCUCUGAAGACGAAGGAGAAUAUGAAGAGGUUAGAAAAGAUCAGGAUUCUGUUGGUGAAAUGAAGGAUGAAGGGGAAGAGACAUUAAAUUAUCCUGAUACUACCAUUGACUUGUCUCACCUUCAACCCCAAAGGUCCAUCCAGAAAUUGGCUUCAAAAGAGGAAUCUUCUAAUUCUAGUGACAGUAAAUCACAGAGCCGGAGACAUUUGUCAGCCAAGGAAAGAAGGGAAAUGAAAAAGAAAAAACUUCCAAGUGACUCAGGAGAUUUAGAAGCGUUAGAGGGAAAGGAUAAAGAAAAAGAAAGUACUGUACACAUUGAAACUCAUCAGAACACAAGCAAAAAUGUUGCGGCUGUGCAGCCAAUGAAACGAGGACAAAAGAGUAAAAUGAAAAAAAUGAAAGAAAAAUACAAAGACCAGGAUGAAGAAGACCGUGAACUUAUCAUGAAGUUGCUGGGGUCUGCAGGUUCAAACAAAGAAGAAAAAGGGAAGAAGGGGAAGAAAGGAAAAACAAAGGACGAACCUGUGAAGAAACAGCCCCAGAAACCUAGAGGUGGACAGAGGGUCUCUGACAACAUUAAGAAAGAAACUCCGUUCCUUGAGGUUAUAACUCAUGAGUUACAAGACUUUGCUGUAGAUGAUCCACAUGAUGACAAGGAAGAGCAAGAUCUGGAUCAACAGGGAAAUGAGGAAAACCUAUUUGAUUCUUUGACAGGCCAGCCACAUCCUGAAGAUGUACUACUGUUUGCCAUUCCAAUAUGUGCCCCUUACACCACCAUGACAAACUACAAAUAUAAAGUGAAACUUACUCCUGGAGUGCAGAAAAAGGGAAAAGCUGCAAAAACAGCCUUGAAUAGUUUCAUGCAUUCCAAAGAAGCAACAGCAAGAGAAAAAGACUUAUUCCGCAGCGUAAAGGACACAGAUUUAUCAAGAAACAUUCCUGGCAAAGUGAAAGUGUCUGCACCCAAUCUUCUGAACGUAAAAAGGAAAUAGCUGAAAUGAAAUUCUAAAAUAUUUGAGAAGAGCCAAUUUUAUAGCCUUUUGGAAGUUCAAAGAUGAAAGCACCAUGUAUCAGGAUUUCCGCAUUAUAAAAAUGAACUAAACAUUGCCUUGCUAUAUUCACCAAAAGGACUUACUUCUUGUUUUUUCCCAGUUUUAUAUAGAGGAAACACUGUCUAUGAUAGGAUUUCCAAAAGUAUUUGUGGACAGUUAAAUGCUAAUUAAUAUACAUCUGUAGUUAUUCUACAUUUUCUUGAAAUUUGGGAGGUUAAUACCAAGUAUUCAUUUCAUGAUGUAAAGAAACUGAACAGUGAAGUGGCUUGAUUGCUUAAACUAUUGACUUGGUAAGUCUACUGUAUAUAACAUCUAAUAUAUAUAUUACAGGCCAAAUGAACUAAACAUUGCCUUGCUAUAUUCACCAAAAGGACUUAAUUCUUGUUUUUUUCCCAGUUUUAUAUAGAGGAAACACUAUGAUAGGAUUUCCUAAAGUAUUUGUGGACAGUUAAAUGCUAAUUAUAUACAUCUGUAGUUAUUCUACAUUUUCUUGAAAUUUGGGAGGUUAAUACCAAGUAUUCAUUUCAUGAUGUAAAGAAACUGAACAGUGAAGUGGCUUGAUUGCUUAAACUAUUGACUUGGUAAGUCUACUGUAUAUAACAUCUAAUAUAUAUAUAUUAUAGGCCAGCUACAAGGGGUUUAAAUAUUUAGGAUUGUGUCUUGAAAACUAAGUAUUGGAGUGGAUUUUCUUCUGCUUUCAUUGAUACUUGUCAGAAAAAAAUAUUAGACCAAAAUGUAAAAUAUAAGUAAUAAUUCUCAUGACUCAGCUUAAUCAUUUCUAUUCAUUUGUAGACCUUCAGGUUUGAUCUUAAUUUUUUCCUUGUAAUCUGAUUCAGUUCUGUACCAUUUUAAUUUCCACCUUUAGUAAUUAAUUACCAAUAUAGCACGUUAGAGUAUCUUAACCUAUAAUACCAGAAGCGCAUUUUAGGCUUACCACUAAAGACUCUAACCCACUUUUCCUCUGUCUCUUAACAGAAUGGAAAAUGAUGUCAUCAUUAUUUCCAUUCCUUCAUGAGCUAUAAAACCUAUUAAUUAAAAAAAAACUUUUUAAUUGACUGGACAGCACCUGCCUGUAUUCAGCAUGACCACUUGCUCCAGCCCCUACACUGAAGCAUUAAGGUCAAAGUACUGAACAGUUGUUGGUCCCUCCACACUUUGUUUUUCCAGCUUCGUCAUAAUGUGAAUAUUAAUGUUUAAAAAAAAAAACCUUUAUUAUAUUGUAUUUACAACACUAGGUUACAUAACUAUAGACUACUCUUGCCAUUAAAAAAAAAAAAAUCUAUAAUGUUUUCAAAAAAUGACUUCAGCAUUUUGAUGAUGGUAAGACUAUAAUGUUUCUACAGAUACAUAUCCUGAAGUUACUGAAAAGAAAAUGUAGCAACCAUUCUUCAGGGUAAAAAGCCCAACCAUUACUUUACUUUAAUAGAGGACAGCUACUGGUGUUAAAUACAUUUAUUGUAAACUUUAGACACAAAAAUAGGUUCUCUAGGCCAUUCACAUGCACAUUAAAACCAACAGGUGCAAACUACAACAAUGCAUAUAAUUAUACAAAUGAUGCCACUCUGUGAUGUUUACAGGAUUGCUGUCCAUGCAAGGUGAUCAUAGGCAUUAUUUAUGAAGCCUUAAGAUCCAGAAGUGUUGUUACUACCAAACCUCUGAUUAACACUGUGAAGUAAGUGUUUUGGAAGGCAGUUCCAUGAGUUGGCUAACAUUUCUUUAAAGCAAAUGACUGCUUCUAAGCUUAGCCUGAAAGUGGACAAGGAAAGAGAAAAGUAAUUUCACUUUACUGUUUGGAAGUACAUUCACUUGAAAAACUACAUAAAACAUCCCUCUUUCUUUCUUCAAAGAUUUUCAUAGGAACUGGUUAUAGCAAUGAAGUUUUAUUGCCCUUAAAUAAUCCAUAAACCUAGUUUUUCGAGAGUGCUAAGUCUUAGGAAACACAAUUUUAAAUAAUCUAAGUGCCAAGUACAAAGUUACUUACCGUACAAGAGAUUUUGGUUGAACUGAAAAUAUUAGUAUUUCAUUACUGUGUGCCUGAAAAAUAAAUAGGAAGAACACAUUUAAAAGCAAAUGCUUUGCAAGUAAGUUUCAGUAAUAAUGUGAAGGUAGUAUACUUACAGCUCUGUGAUGGACAAGCAAGUUGUUGGCACAUCCACCAAAAACAAUUACUUCUCCUUCAUCGCUGGCACAAGCUGUGUGCCAUAACCUGCAUUUAAAACAAAAACGAGUUUGAAGCCACCCAGAACACCAGUUGGCCAUUUUAUACUACAGAAUAGAGCUAUGAAAUAAAGACUAGCGAUCUUAAGGUAGUUCAGACCAAAACAUCAUGGCGAGAAGUAAAAUCUUAAGGGAAAGUAGCAAAAGCAGAUCAAUCAAUAUCUAUUUUAUCUGGAUAUUAUUUUCUCUCUCUGGUCGUUCUCAUUUAUGCAAUGAGGAGUUUGAACUGAACGAUCUGUUCUCUAGGUCUUUGUUAGCAAUAAAAAUCGUAUGGGA